ACAUAAAUCUGACCAAGAACACAAGCAUCUUAAUUUGAAUCCACAAAGUUUCAUGUAAUGAAAAGAAAUACAUAAUUUUAAUUCAACCCGAGUGUUUUCCAAGAAGAUUGUAUUUGCUUAAAUUGCUACAGUAAUUCAAGAGACAGCCCUGUCUGGACACAGAGUUACUGUGGAUUUUUAAGAGACUCAGUUAAAGAAUUUAGGAAUUUCUGAUUCAUUUAAAGGAUUUACAAAUUCAUCAACCCCUGAAAACUAAAGCAAAUUGAACAGGAAAAAAAAAAAGAAGAUGGGUUUUUUAAGUCCAAUAUAUGUUAUUUUCUUCUUUUUUGGAGUCAAAGUACAUUGCCAAUAUGAAACUUAUCAGUGGGAUGAAGACUAUGACCAAGAGCCAGAUGAUGAUUACCAAACAGGAUUCCCAUUUCGUCAAAAUGUAGACUACGGAGUUCCUUUUCAUCAGUAUACUUUAGGCUGUGUCAGUGAAUGCUUCUGUCCAACUAACUUUCCAUCAUCAAUGUACUGUGAUAAUCGCAAACUCAAGACUAUCCCAAAUAUUCCGAUGCACAUUCAGCAACUCUACCUUCAGUUCAAUGAAAUUGAGGCUGUGACUGCAAAUUCAUUCAUCAAUGCAACUCAUCUUAAAGAAAUUAACCUCAGCCACAACAAAAUUAAAUCUCAAAAGAUUGAUUAUGGUGUGUUUGCUAAGCUUCCAAAUCUACUACAACUUCAUCUAGAGCAUAAUAAUUUAGAAGAAUUUCCAUUUCCUCUUCCUAAAUCUCUGGAAAGACUCCUUCUUGGUUACAAUGAAAUCUCCAAACUGCAGACAAAUGCUAUGGAUGGGCUAGUAAACUUGACCAUGCUUGAUCUCUGUUAUAAUUAUCUUCAUGAUUCUCUGCUAAAAGACAAAAUCUUUGCCAAAAUGGAAAAACUAAUGCAGCUCAACCUCUGCAGUAACAGAUUAGAAUCAAUGCCUCCUGGUUUGCCUUCUUCACUUAUGUAUCUGUCUUUAGAAAAUAAUUCAAUUUCUUCUAUACCCGAAAAAUACUUCGACAAACUUCCAAAACUUCAUACUCUAAGAAUGUCACACAACAAACUACAAGACAUCCCAUAUAAUAUUUUUAAUCUUCCCAACAUUGUAGAACUCAGUGUUGGACACAACAAAUUGAAGCAAGCAUUCUAUAUUCCAAGAAAUUUGGAACACCUAUACCUACAAAAUAAUGAAAUAGAAAAGAUGAAUCUUACAGUGAUGUGUCCUUCUAUUGACCCACUACAUUACCACCAUUUAACAUACAUUCGUGUGGACCAAAAUAAACUAAAAGAACCAAUAAGCUCAUACAUCUUCUUCUGCUUCCCUCAUAUACACACUAUUUAUUAUGGUGAACAACGAAGCACUAAUGGUCAAACAAUACAACUAAAGACACAAGUUUUCAGGAGAUUUCCAGAUGAUGAUGAUGAAAGUGAAGAUCACGAUGAUCCUGACAAUGCUCAUGAGAGCCCAGAACAAGAAGGAGCAGAAGGGCACUUUGACCUUCAUUAUUAUGAAAAUCAAGAAUAGCAAGAAACUAUAUAGGUAUACACUUACGACUUCACAAAACCUAUACUUAAUAUAGUAAAUCUAAGUAAACAUGUAUUACUCAAAGUAAUAUAUUUAGAAUUAUGUAUUAGUAUAAGAUCAGAAUUGAAUUUAAGUUGUUGGUGACAUCUGCAUCAUUUCAUAGGAUUAGAACUUACUCAAAAUAAUGUAAAUCUUUAAAAAUAUAAAUUAGAAUGACAAGUGGGAAUCAUAAAUUAAACGUUAAUGGUUUCUUAUGCUCUUUUUAAAUAUAGAAAUAUCAUGUUAAAGAAAGUGAGUGUAUCAUUUCUAUUAACAGUAAUUUUUCUAAAAAUGAGGAAGGAAGUAGCAUUAGCAGUAAAGACCCACAGGCCAUGACCUUUUUGAUCACUCUGAGGACAAUAUUUAAAUGACAGGAAGGUAUAUUAAUGUAACAAGCAUUCAUUUAAGGAAUAGACCAUUUUCUCUGACCUCUUCUUCAGGAAAGCUUUCACACUGGUAUUUGUGAUCUCACCAUUAUGACAUCCAUCCCCCUAGCUCACCACAUAGCACAUAGAAUGAUAUUUUUGAUUUGUAAGAGGCCAUCCAGGUACUAAGGACCCAAGGCAUACAGAUUCACAAAAUUAACUAAUCUUUUUGCCUCAGAAUACCAAAACAACAAAAUUAUAAAGCUGUAUUUGGACAACUAAAAAACACCAAACUAUCUCAUUGCAAUUUGUAUUUUAGCAGAUUUCAGCAACUAUCCUAAACAAUGUUAUUGUGUUCCAUUUUAACUGGGAUAAAUGUUUUUGUAAAAAUACAACCAUAGAAAGGCCUCUUUGUUACAAAAUGAUUUGCAAAGAAAUAACUGCUUUGUUUGCAAGAUUAAAUUAGUGUUGGCAAAAUAAAGUUCUAAAGAUAAUACUAAACACUUUAUGCUUAUCAGCCAAUAUCUACAUAAGCUAAAAUUGAAUACAGUUCCUUUAUAAUUUGAAUGACAGGUUUUAACAUCUUCUUUAAAACCUUAAAAAUCACUUUUUCGUUAAUGUAUUAUUUUUAAGUAUUGUAAGUGUGCCUUACAAUGAUGAUUAUCUAACUGCUGUGAUGAACUCUCUUGAUAUACCAUGCUAAUGUUUCAUAGAAUUUCUCAGAUAAGGGACAAAUACCAAUCUAGGGCUGCCUAUACAAAUGAUAACAAUUCUGACAAUAUGCAACAGACAGACAAGUCAAACUAUACUUCAGAAAUAGUUUUCAAGCUUGCAAGUCUUUUUUUCUGGAAAUACCAGUUUAAAGUGAAGUCUUUAAUGCUCUUUACAUCUUUGAGGAAUUAUUAGCAUUAUCAGAACCAGAACGCCCACCUGUUCCCAGGGACAACCUCAAGAAUCCAGGAUGAAUAUGAAGAAAACUCCAUUCAUUCGUCUAAUCAACAUUCAUCAAGUCCUUUCUUAUAUAGGGCUUGGCAAUAAGGGAUCAAUAAACAAAGUACAAUGUGCAACUAUGAUGCCACAAUAUGGGCAAAGCACAUUUUCAACAGAGGUUAAAAAAAAAAUCUUAAGGCCCACCUCCCUUUUCUUGCAAUUUUUAAAUACAGGAUAUAAAUUCAAACAUUAAGAGUUAAUACGUGGAAAAUACUAUAGGUGUUUUAGAAAACAAAGAUAAGACAAUUCCUAACCUAGAGCAAUUUAAAAUUUAUGAGCCAUUAGGGAAAUGCAAAUAAAUGAGAUAUUACUAUGUGCUCACUAGGAUAGCUGAAAUCAAAAGGCAGACAAAUAACAAGUGUUGGCAAGAUGUGGAAAAAUUGGAGCCUUCAUACACCUUUGGAAGGAGUGUAAAUACUGCAGCUGCUUAGAAAAGCAGUAUGGAAGUUCCUUAAAAAGUUAGUUACAUAUAGUCGGGCGCAUUAGCUCACACCUGUAAUCCCAGCACUUUGGAAGGCCGAGUUAGGUGGAUCACCUGGGGUCGGGAGUUUGAGACCAGCCUGACCAACAUGGAGAAACCCCAUCUCUACUAAAAAUACAAAAUAAUUAGCCAGGCAUGGUGGCACAUGCCUGUAAUCCCGGCUACUUGCGAGGCUGAGGCAGGAGAAUUGCCUAAACCCAAGAGGCAGAAGUUGCGGUGAGCCAAGACCAUGCCAUUGCACUCCAGCCUGGGCAACAAGAGCAAAAGUCCAUAUCAAAAAAAAAAAAAAAAAAAAAAAAAAGCUUAGUUACAUAUAACCCAGCGAUUCCAUUCCUAACUAUAUACCCAAUAGAACUGAACACACAUGUUCACACCAAAAUUUGCAUAUAAAUGUCCACAGCAGCAUUAUCCACAAGGUAGAAAUCACCCACAUGUCCAUCAAUGGAUAAACAAAAUGUGGUAUAUCCAUUUCAUGGAAUAUUAUUCAGCCAUAUCCAAAGGUAGAAACCACGCAAAUGUCCAUCAAUGGAUACACAAAAUGUGAUAUAUCCAUACAGUGGAAUAUUAUUCAGCAAUAAAAAGUAACGAAGCACUGACAUAUGCUACAACAUGGAUAACCUUGAAAACAUUAUGCUCAGUGAAAGAAGUCAGUCGUAAAAAGACACAAAUUGUAUGAUUCCAUCUUUAUGAAAUGUCCAGAACUGGGAAAUCUAUGGAGACAAAGACUAUUGGUUGCCUAGAGCUGGGGAUCAUGGGAAUGGGGAAAGUGAGAAGUAACUGCUAAUGGGUAUAUGGUUUCUUUUUUGGAGUAAUGAAAAUGUUCCAAAAUUGACUGUGGUGAUGGUUGUACAAAUGCAAAAACACUAAGUACUAUUAAAUUGUAUACUUUAGGCUGGG